AGCUCAGCUCCGGAGAGCCGGCGGCGCGGCGGGCAUGGCUCGGGUGGCGUGGGGGCUGCUGUGGUUGCUGCUGGGCAGCGCCGGGGCGCAGUACGAGAAGUACAGCUUCCGGGGCUUCCCGCCCGAGGACCUGAUGCCGCUGGCCGCGGCGUACGGGCACGCUCUGGAGCAGUACGAGGGAGAGAGCUGGCGCGAGAGCGCGCGCUACCUGGAGGCGGCGCUGCGGCUGCACCGGCUCCUGCGCGACAGCGAGGCCUUCUGCCACGCCAACUGCAGCGGCCCCGCGCCCGCGGCCAAGCCCGAUCCCGACGGCGGCCGCGCAGACGAGUGGGCCUGCGAGCUGCGGCUCUUCGGCCGCGUCCUGGAGCGAGCCGCCUGCCUGCGGCGCUGCAAGCGGACGCUGCCCGCCUUCCAGGUGCCCUACCCGCCGCGGCAGCUGCUGCGUGACUUCCAGAGCCGCCUGCCCUACCAGUACCUGCACUACGCGCUGUUCAAGGCUAACCGGCUGGAGAAGGCGGUGGCGGCGGCCUACACCUUCCUCCAGAGGAACCCGAAGCACGAGCUGACCGCCAAGUAUCUCAACUACUAUCAGGGGAUGCUGGACGUCGCCGACGAGUCCCUCACGGACCUAGAGGCCCAGCCCUACGAGGCCGUGUUCCUCCGGGCUGUGAAGCUCUACAACAGCGGGGAUUUCCGCAGCAGCACGGAGGACAUGGAGCGGGCCUUGUCAGAGUACCUGGCAGUCUUUGCCCGGUGCCUGGCCGGCUGUGAAGGGGCCCAUGAGCAGGUGGACUUCAAGGACUUCUACCCGGCCAUAGCAGGUAUCUGCCACCCAGACCACGGUGGGCGGUCCUCUCACCCACAGGGCCCGGUAAGGCAGAUGUCCCCUUCAUGCACGUGGAGCACUGCGAAUGCGGAGGAGCCAGCCGGGAGGAAGGCCUUGUCUGUUGAGAAAGACGCUGGGUGCAGGGGCCCCAGCUGGGAGUGUCCAAGGGGCUGGAUCAAUCUCUUUGCAGAGUCCCUGCAGUGCAAGGUGGACUGUGAGGCCAAUUUGACCCCCAAUGUGGGUGGCUACUUCGUGGACAAGUUCGUGGCCACCAUGUACCACUACCUGCAGUUUGCCUACUAUAAGUUGAAUGAUGUGCGCCAGGCUGCCCGCAGCGCCGCCAGCUACAUGCUCUUCGACCCCAAGGACAGCGUCAUGCAGCAGAACCUGGUGUAUUACCGGUUCCACCGGGCUCGCUGGGGCCUGGAAGAGGAGGACUUCCAGCCCCGGGAGGAGGCCAUGCUCUACCACAACCAGACCGCCGAGCUGCGGGAGCUGCUGGAGUUCACCCACAUGUACCUGCAGUCAGAUGAUGAGAUGGAGCUGGAGGAGACAGAACCGCCCCUGGAGCCUGAGGAUGCCCUAUCUGACGCCGAGUUUGAGGGGGAGGGUGACUACGAGGAGGGCAUGUAUGCUGACUGGUGGCAGGAGCCGGAUGCCAAGGGUGACGAGGCCGAGGCUGAGCCAGAGCCUGAACUCGCAUGAGAAGGGGACACCCCACACCGCUCAAGCUUGGGAAGCCUGGUGCCGAUGGCCCCACCCUCACCAGCCUGGGCAGCAGCAAGAACUAUUUAUUAAAAACUUAAGAUGGGCCAGGUGCGGUGGCUCACACCUGUAAUCCCAGCAUUUUGGGAGGCCAAGGUGGGUGGAUCACUUGAGGCCAGGAGUUCAAGACCAGCCUGGCCAACAUGAUGAGACCUCCGUCUCUACUAAAAUACAUAAAUUAGCCGGGUGUGGUGGCAGGCGCCUGAAAUCCCAGCUACUCAAGAGGCUGAGGCAGGAGAAUCGCUUGAACCUGGGAGGCAAAGGUUGCAGUGAACUGAGAUUGCGCCACCGCACUCCAGCCUGGGCGACAGAGCGAGACUCCAUCUUUAAAAAAAAACAAGACGGGCCGGCACGGUGGCUCACGCCUGUAAUCCCAGCACUGAGAGGCCGAUCACUUGAGGUCAGGAGUUCAAGACCAGCCUGGCCAACAUGGUGAAACCCCAUCUCUACUAAAAAAUACAAAAAUUAGCCAGGCAUGGUGGCACACACCUGUAAUCGUAGCUGAGGCAGGAGAAUCGCCUGAACCCAGGAGGCGGAGCUUGCAGUGAGCCGAGAUCGUGCCACUGCACUCCAGCCUGGGCGACAGAGUGAGACUCCAUCUCAAAAAAAAAAAAAAAAACUUAAGAUGGACACAGCUGACUGGACCCCCAUCCUGCCUCACCCAUGGGUGCUGCACCCCAGACCCAUCCUGCCACUUCUAUGUCUCUGGACCACAGGAUGGUGGUGGCAUUGCAGGUUGGCAAGUGGGCUGAUGGGGUCCGCCCUCCUCACUGCUGAGCUCCUCACCUGGACAGUCUCCUGGACAAGGAGUUUCCAGCUGCUGGCUGGAGUCUCAGGCCAAAUUGCAGAGGGUCCUCCAGGGUCCUGAAGAGCACUGGACUAAGAGUCUAGUGGUUCCAGGGCCCUGACCAGUAGGUGCUCAAUAAAUGUUUGUUGUUGAAUGA